GCACGGAAGCCGGGACCCGCGCCCAGCCGGGCCACGGAGUUUGGGGACCUCCGGGACUGGGCCGGCCCCGCGCGCCAGCCAUGUUGCCUGCGUCGGAGGAAGCGUGCGGGGAGCAGGGGUCGAGGGCCAAGAUGGCCUCUGCGCCUAGGGGUUGGGAGCGGCGCCGAGCCCCUCGCGCUCCUCGGGAAGCCACCGGGCCCGAGGGAAAAGCCGCGGCAUCCUUAGGCCGGACCCGGGGCUCGCUGGCCACACUGCCCGCUUGGGGAAUUACCCUGCUCGAGGAGGAGGCGGCGGCUUUCCAGGCCAGUCAGUGUGUGGCCCUUAGGCAACAGGUGUAUUAUUGGGAUACCUGGAAAAGAGAAACGUUUCCCAUGAAGGCACUUAUGGUGUUUUUUGGUGAUUCUUGGUGUGAUAGAAAACUAGGCGUUCCCAAGUGUAACAAUAGUAACAGUAGUUCUUUUGCACUGUACAUAUGAGGUGCUUCUGUGUGUGUGUGUGUGUUUUUCCGAGACGGAGUCUGGCUCUGUCCCCCAGUGCAGUGGCAUCAUCUGGGCUCACUGCAACCUCUGCCUCCCGGGUUCAAGCGAUUCUCCUGCUCAGCCUCCCGAAUAGCUGGGAUUACAGGCACCCACUAGUAUGCACAGCUAAUUUUUGUAUUUUUAGUAGAGACAGGGUUUUGCCAUUUGGUCAGGCUGGUCUCGAACUCCUGACCUCAGGUGAUUCGCCCGCCUUGGCCUCCCAAAGUGCUGGGAUUACAGGCGUAAGCCACCACACCCAGCCUUUAUGAAUAUUUUCUUAGUGGUGCUUUAAAAUAGACAUCUUAAGUGUGUGUGGGAGGCAGAGAUAUUUCCUCAAACAAAGCAACACUUUUUUUUUGGUCGUUUUGCAAUUUAUUUAGUUAUUAGGGGCCUCCUUUGUUAGGUGACGGAGCAGAGGAUAGGGAGAUCGGUAAGACAUGAUUCUCCACCUUUUGGCAGUUUCCAGGCCAUUUCGGGAAAUAGUGGGCAGCAGUGCCUCCUGCACGUGAGGCACUGUGGUAAAAGCAUUCUGUAUUUUCUCAUUUAAUUAUCCCAACAACUCUAAAAGGCAGGCCUUAGUAGAACUCCAUUUUAAAAGUGGGCAAAUGCCGUGGGGGAAACGUUGCAGGUGGGCUUGCUUGCAAACUGCUUCAGCUAAUAUGGGAAGGAGUAUCAGAAGCAGCGGUCCUUGAUAUUCCAGAACCAGAUUUGGGGAAUUUUUCUGGACUUUUCUACCAUUGACUAGUAACUGUAGCCUGAUACAAGAUUUCCCGCAUUUUGCUUGAUAUCAAGGUAAAAUUCUUGUUUUCUUCUAAAGGUAGUGUUGGAAUUACUACCUUUUCAAAAUAGUAUAUUACUUUUAACCACAUAAAUGAUCUGAUGUAAUAUCUUUCAUCUUCCUAGGAACCUCCCAGAAGGAAGUUUUCUUCAGUUGCAUUUUAAGGCUUAUUUGAUUGGAAUAUUAAUGGAUCUUUUUCAUCAAAUUACUAUUUAUGGAAAUAAGAGAGUAAACAGACCAUGCAGAUUUAUGUUAGGCUUUUUGUUUUAACCCCUAGGCUUGCCGCUGUUCCGUAACCCAGUGAUUCCAGUCUUGGCUGUGGUAUGAAUCACUUAGGGAUCCUAUUAAAACACAGAUUCUGAUUGGGAGGUCAGGAGUGGGGCCUGGGAUUCUGCCUUUCUAACAGGCUCACAGAUUGGUUUAUCUUGGAAGCUAAAGGGCAUUGCUCAUCCUGAAGAUCAGCUGACCAUUGACAAUCAGCCAUGUCAUCCAGGCCUCUUGAAAGUCCACCUCCUUACAGGCCUGAUGAAUUCAAACCGAAUCAUUAUGCACCAAGCAAUGACAUAUAUGGUGGAGAGAUGCAUGUUCGACCAAUGCUCUCUCAGCCAGCCUACUCUUUUUACCCAGAAGAUGAAAUUCUUCACUUCUACAAAUGGACCUCUCCUCCAGGAGUGAUUCGGAUCCUGUCUAUGCUCAUUAUUGUGAUGUGCAUUGCCAUCUUUGCCUGUGUGGCCUCCACGCUUGCCUGGGACAGAGGCUAUGGAACUUCCCUUUUAGGAGGUAGUGUAGGCUACCCUUAUGGAGGAAGUGGCUUUGGUAGCUACGGAAGUGGCUAUGGCUAUGGCUAUGGUUAUGGCUAUGGCUACGGAGGCUAUACAGACCCAAGAGCAGCAAAGGGCUUCAUGUUGGCCAUGGCUGCCUUUUGUUUCAUUGCCGCGUUGGUGAUCUUUGUUACCAGUGUUAUAAGAUCUGAAAUGUCCAGAACAAGAAGAUACUACUUAAGUGUGAUAAUAGUGAGUGCUAUCCUGGGCAUCAUGGUGUUUAUUGCCACAAUUGUCUAUAUAAUGGGAGUGAACCCAACUGCUCAGUCUUCUGGAUCUCUAUAUGGUUCACAAAUAUAUGCCCUCUGCAACCAAUUUUAUACACCUGCAGCUACUGGACUCUACGUGGAUCAGUAUUUGUAUCACUACUGUGUUGUGGAUCCCCAGGAGGCCAUUGCCAUUGUACUGGGGUUCAUGAUUAUUGUGGCUUUUGCUUUAAUAAUUUUCUUUGCUGUGAAAACUCGAAGAAAGAUGGACAGGUAUGACAAGUCCAAUAUUUUGUGGGACAAGGAACACAUUUAUGAUGAGCAGCCCCCCAAUGUCGAGGAGUGGGUUAAAAAUGUGUCUGCAGGCACACAGGACGUGCCUUCACCCCCAUCUGACUAUGUGGAAAGAGUUGACAGUCCCAUGGCAUACUCUUCCAAUGGCAAAGUGAAUGACAAGCGGUUUUAUCCAGAGUCUUCCUAUAAAUCCACGCCGGUUCCUGAAGUGGUUCAGGAGCUUCCAUUAACUUCGCCUGUGGAUGACUUCAGGCAGCCUCGUUACAGCAGCGGUGGUAACUUUGAGACACCUUCAAAAAGAGCACCUGCAAAGGGAAGAGCAGGAAGGUCAAAGAGAACAGAGCAAGAUCACUAUGAGACAGACUACACAACUGGCGGCGAGUCCUGUGAUGAGCUGGAGGAGGACUGGAUCAGGGAAUAUCCACCUAUCACUUCAGAUCAACAAAGACAACUGUACAAGAGGAAUUUUGACACUGGCCUACAGGAAUACAAGAGCUUACAAUCAGAACUUGAUGAGAUCAAUAAAGAACUCUCCCGUUUGGAUAAAGAAUUGGAUGACUAUAGAGAAGAAAGUGAAGAGUACAUGGCUGCUGCUGAUGAAUACAAUAGACUGAAGCAAGUGAAGGGAUCUGCAGAUUACAAAAGUAAGAAGAAUCAUUGCAAGCAGUUAAAGAGCAAAUUGUCACACAUCAAGAAGAUGGUUGGAGACUAUGAUAGACAGAAAACAUAGAAGGCUGAUGCCAAGUUGUUUGAGAAAUUAAGUAUCUGACAUCUCUGCAAUCUUCUCAGAAGGCAAAUGACUUUGGACCAUAACCCCGGAAGCCAAACCUCUGUGAGCAUCACAAAGUUUUGGUUGCUUUAACAUCAUCAGUAUUGAAGCAUUUUAUAAAUCGCUUUUGAUAAUCAACUGGGCUGAACACUCCAAUUAAGGAUUUUAUGCUUUAAACAUUGGUUCUUGUAUUAAGAAUGAAAUACUGUUUGAGGUUUUUAAGCCUUAAAGGAAGGUUCUGGUGUGAACUAAACUUUCACACCCCAGACGAUGUCUUCAUACCUACAUGUAUUUGUUUGCAUAGGUGAUCUCAUUUAAUCCUCUCAACCACCUUUCAGAUAACUGUUAUUUAUAAUCACUUUUUUCCACAUAAGGAAACUGGGUUCCUGCAAUGAAGUCUCUGAAGUGAAACUGCUUGUUUCCUAGCACACACUUUUGGUUAAGUCUGUUUUAUGACUUCAUUAAUAAUAAAUUCCCUGGCCUUUCAUAUUUUAGCUACUAUAUAUGUGAUGAUCUACCAGCCUCCCUAUUUUUUUUCUGUUAUAUAAAUGGUUAAAAGAGGUUUUUCUUAAAUAAUAAAGAUCAUGUAAAAGUAACAAAUGUGUGAAAUUUAAAGAUUGUAAAUAUAUAUUUACUUUUUUAAGAUCAAAGUUUAAACCCCGUGGUUAGAAUUUUGUGUGUUUUUAAAUACUUUUUAUCUUUUUGCAUGCCUUUUUUAAAAAACCAACUAGAACUUUUCAUUAUAUCAGAAUAUCUGAUUACAUUUAUAAUUCAAUUGUGACUUGAACUGUAUCUUACAGGAAUGUUCAAUUUCUAUACAUAUUUUAUAAGGUAUUAAACCUGGUGUUUUCUUUCCAUAAUAACCUGUUUGAUGUUAUUAGUGCUGUUAACAUACAGCAAUGGAAAACCACACUCAGGAGUUGUAUCUGUUGUUGUUUAUACUCCUUUGGAUGCUGUGCUGGUUAGUCGUUUCCCAUUCCUUUGGCUGUAAGAAUGCUGAUAUGUCUGGGAAUAGAAUGCUAUACCACGAAAUACCAAAUAAUUUCAAAUGGUGCCCUUAAAUUGUAUCACUUUUUUAAAAAUUCAGAUUCUUAUUAGUAAAAUUAGUUGAUAGCACUGUGCUGACCAAGUUGAUUGUGAUCAUCCCAGCUUAGACUUUUCUAAAAACUUUUUUUUAGAAUAAUCUAUAAACUGAACUUUAGUAUGCAUUUCAGAUAUUUAGGUAUAUAAUUUUUUUUUUUUUUUUGAGACAGAGUCUCACUCUCACCCAGGCUGGAAUGCAGUGGUGCUAUCUUGGCUCACUGCAACCUCCACCUCCCGGGUUCAAGCAAUUCUCCUGCCUCAGCCUCUCGAGUAGUUGAGACUACAGGUGCCCAUCACCAUGCCUGGCUAAUUUUUGUAUUUUUAAUAGAGACGGGGUUUUACCAUAUUGGCCAGGUUGGUCUUGAACUCCUGACCUUGUGGUCUGCCUGCCUCGGCCUCCCAAAGUGCUGGGAUUACAGGCGUGAGCCACCAUGCCUGGCCUAAGUGUGUGUGUGUGUGUGUGUGUAUUUUUUUUUUUUUUUUUUUGAGAUGGAGUUUUGCUCUUGUUGAACAGGCUGGAGUGCAAUGUCGCGAUCUCAGCUCACCACAACCUCCGCCUCCCAGGUUCAAACAAUUCUCCUGCCUCGGCCUCCCGAGUAGCUGGGAUUACAGGCAUGCGCCACCACACCUGGCUAAUUUUUUUUUUGUAUUUUUAGUAGAGAUGGGGUUUCUCCAUGUUGGUCAGGCUGGUCUCGAACUCCUGACCUCAGGUGAUCCAUCCACCUCGGCCUCCCAAAGUGCUGGGAUUAGAGGCGUGAGCCACUGUGCCCGGCCUAUAAUUUUUGAUAGAUGAUUUUGAAUUAUUUUCCAGAGAUAAAAUUUUAAAUGUUUCCAUUAUAUCACUGAUUUAUUUCUGCAAAUUGAAUAAAUUCUUAAUUUUCUGCAUGCACAUAAUACAAAAGGUAUUUUCAUAGUUUUGGAUUUAUACCAAAUGAAAAGGAUUCUCUUGAUGAGCACCUUUAACUGAUUUUUCUGUUAAAGUUUUAACAAUUUGUUCUUGGAAGUCAGUUCGUGAAGGCAAGUUUGUCAGUAUUUUCACAAAACUAUUCAGCUGAAUCCAGAAAGUGAAACAGCAAGAAUUUGCAUUGUAAAAUUGUGUUAUAAAAUUGGACUUUGAAAUUUCAAAAAUAAGAAAAAUUUUCAUGUGUAUUUAUACUAAAUACCGUUUUAGGAAACUAGGAUCAGGGUGUUUCUGUUGGCGUUGGCAUUAACUAGCUGGAUGUAAAUUUGAAAAGCCACUCAAGCAGCUUCCUAGUCUAGAAAGUCAGAGGUUUAGAUUAGAUUUCCGACAUCCCUUCCAUUUCUGACCUGUAGUUCUUGUCUGGAAUUCUGCUUUGUUAUAAACUAUUGUUCUAAGGAGUUUGUUGUGAUAGCACAUAGUUCAUUUUGUAAAGAUUCCCUGCGUAUAAAGUGAUGCCCUACAUAUGUGAUUUUGUAUUAAAAGUAUAUAGGAUCAUUAUUUUAUUUUGAAAAAUUUAAAUACAGAAAAGUAUAAAAUAUAAGUACCAUCCGCCCAGAAAUAACAUGUGUUAAUGUUUUGUCAUAUGUGCUUUAUAUUUUUUGAAAUAAAGUGAAGUCAACUAGUAUUUAUAGUAAAUAAGUUACAUACACAUAAGUACAUAUAUGAUAUUUAAUCCUCACAACGAUCUUUUGACAUGUGACCAUUUCUUAUUCUUCUUUUAUAGACAAGGAACUAAUGAUAUGAUAGAUUAACUGGCUGUUGUCACACUAGCAAGUGGCAAAACAAGGGAUUAGGAUCUUAGUCUCUUCAACUGUUAGAUUCUAUACUUCCAUCCUGUGUUGACUUUGUUAAUGGAUUGGAUAAUGUGAGAUCACUCUGAUGUAAAUAAAGUAUCCUAUAUUAAUUUCGAGUGCAUUUUAAGUACUUGUAACAUAAAUGCUUCCUGUGAAACAUCUGUAAAGACCUGAAUGGGUACAUGUGUGUAAAGAAGAAUCAGGGCAGAAAAGUGCUUUUAUCAUGGCUCCGGGGACCUUAGCUUCAGUUGGUGUUGUGAGAAUUCCUCACACAAGGACAUUCUCCUUGCUUCAGCAUCAGGAUGGAAGUGUUUCUCAUCUGGACUUUUUCAAAGACUCAGCUGGAGGAAUCAGAAUUCAUAAUUUCCUGGCAGCUCAUGAUUCUGCUACACUACACCAUGCCAUCUCUUGUGUGAAAGGACAGAUUUGAUGGAGGACUAUGUCAUCCCUCAUGCGUUUCUUAUUGUCUACAUUUAUUCUAAUGGGAAGAAGUGAGCAAAAACACCUCAAUAAUUUGGGUAGUUUUUAGAAAACCUUGUUAGUAAAUUAGAAUAGUGCCACUUUGGCAUUAUGAGAAAGAAGCAUGGAUACAUAACUAGGGUUUUGUGUAUGACUACAACGAAAUGCAGAAUGGUGUCUCCAAAAGGUUUCCAGUUGCUGCCACAAGAACUGCUUGGUAUUGCCUACAUGUGUUGUCCUAUUUUUGCUUUGCCCUUCUGCAGUUACUUGCUGUGGGACCUUGGAGAAAUUAACUUAGCCUCUCUGUACUUCAGUUUUUUGUAUUUGUAAAAAUAUAUUUGUAAUAAUCUCAUAGUUAAGAAGGUAGUUAAUGUGUGACUCAGUCCUUGUCUAAAAGUAAAUAUGCCUAGCUACCCCCAUCUUCCAAAGCCAGAAGGUGAAACUUUAACAAGUUUUCUAAAAGCAAAUUGUGUUUUUUAAAAGUGCAUGUGUCAUCCAAUCCCAUAUGAUUGAUCUGUGCUGGGUGCAGCCUUAGAAUGUAAAUUCUUUUGAAUUCUAGGCAGAGAAUGCAGGAUUGGCAUUCUAAAUAUUUGUACAUGAUAAACAAAUGCUUCUUUAGGUUACAGCAAAUAGUUUACUUAUCAAGAUCACGAUUGUUAGAUACUGUUGUCAAUUACAGAGGUUUUAGAUGAGGCUUUCUGGAAUGAUUUAGUUUCCCUGUAAGGGAGCCUGUCUAUUGGAAUAGACAGGUUCACUUCUCCCAGUCUUUCAAGUUGCAUGCUUUUUAUAUCUGAUUCCACUGGCUGAGCUGAUUGUGAAUGUCCUAACCCUGUUGAUAGUGUCUGGCCACUCAUGGGCAAAGAACAGAUUAUCCAUUCUUUAUAGUUGUCUUUUAGUUUUACAAGUUGAAAAAACAUCUGAGUAGGUUAGAUAAUUUAUUCUACCACUUUGUAAAUGAUUAGAAUAUGUCAGUCAUAAUCAUGCCAAGAGAUUAUGGAUUUAUGCAUAUUUUGUUUUGCUGUAGUACCAUUCCUAGUUGAAUCUUAACAUCCAUGUCUAAAAUCUAUACAGAACAAAUAUUACAGUUGGGAAAACUG